CUUCCCAGCCCCCGGCCUAGCUCUGCGAACGGUGACUGCCCAUCCUUGGCCGCAAUGAGCCACCACCCGUCGGGCCUCCGGGCCGGCUUCAGCUCCACCUCAUACCGCCGUACCUUCGGUCCACCGCCCUCACUAUCCCCCGGGGCCUUCUCCUACUCGUCCAGCUCCCGCUUCUCCAGCAGCCGCCUGCUGGGCUCCGCGUCCCCGAGCUCCUCGGUGCGCCUGGGCAGCUUCCGUAGCCCCCGAGCGGGAGCGGGCGCCCUCCUGCGCCUGCCCUCGGAGCGCCUCGACUUCUCCAUGGCCGAGGCCCUCAACCAGGAGUUCCUGGCCACGCGCAGCAACGAGAAGCAGGAGCUGCAGGAGCUCAACGACCGCUUCGCCAACUUCAUCGAGAAGGUACGCUUUCUGGAGCAGCAGAACGCGGCCCUGCGCGGGGAGCUGAGCCAAGCCCGGGGCCAGGAGCCGGCGCGCGCCGACCAGCUGUGCCAGCAGGAGCUGCGCGAGCUGCGGCGAGAGCUGGAGCUGUUGGGCCGCGAGCGUGACCGGGUGCAGGUGGAGCGCGACGGGCUGGCGGAGGACCUGGCGGCGCUCAAGCAGAGGUUGGAGGAGGAGACGCGCAAGCGGGAGGACGCGGAGCACAACCUCGUGCUCUUCCGCAAGGACGUGGACGAUGCCACUCUGUCCCGCCUGGAACUAGAGCGCAAGAUUGAGUCUCUGAUGGAUGAGAUUGAGUUCCUCAAGAAGCUGCACGAGGAGGAGCUGCGAGACCUGCAGGUGAGUGUGGAGAGCCAGCAGGUGCAGCAGGUGGAGGUGGAAGCCACGGUGAAGCCCGAGCUGACGGCAGCGCUGAGGGACAUCCGCGCGCAGUACGAGAGCAUCGCCGCGAAGAACCUGCAGGAGGCGGAGGAGUGGUACAAGUCCAAGUACGCGGACCUGUCCGACGCUGCCAACCGGAACCACGAGGCCCUGCGCCAGGCCAAGCAGGAGAUGAACGAGUCCCGACGCCAGAUCCAGAGUCUAACGUGCGAGGUGGACGGGCUGCGCGGCACGAACGAGGCGCUGCUCAGGCAGUUGAGAGAGCUGGAGGAGCAGUUCGCCCUGGAGGCGGGGGGCUACCAGGCGGGCGCUGCGCGGCUCGAGGAGGAGCUGCGACAGCUAAAAGAGGAGAUGGCGCGGCACCUGAGGGAGUACCAGGAGCUCCUCAACGUCAAGAUGGCCCUGGACAUCGAGAUCGCCACCUACCGCAAGCUGCUGGAGGGCGAGGAGAGCCGGAUCUCCGUGCCCGUCCAUUCUUUUGCCUCCUUAAAUAUAAAGACGACUGUGCCUGAGGUGGAGCCUCCCCAGGACAGCCACAGCCGGAAGACGGUUCUGAUCAAGACCAUUGAGACCCGGAAUGGGGAGGUGGUGACAGAGUCCCAGAAGGAGCAGCGCAGUGAGCUGGACAAGUCUUCUGCCCACAGUUACUGAACCCCUUGGUCCGGAGCCUUGACUCUGCCCUAGGCCUGCUCAAAGCCCAAACCCUAAGACCACUCCUGAAUUGUCUCCUCUCCCUCUGCAUGUGUCUAAAAGGUGGUACCAGGCAUCCCUUUCCUGGCUUAUGGCCAAGCCCUACCCGGCCAGCAGUCGCUGGGCCUCUCCCUGCCCUGACACUUGAUGUGACCUAUGUGCUUCCCUUUUCAUGUCCCGAUAAGAAGCCAAUGAUCCCCCCUCAGGACAAAUCUACUCCAGCCACGAUGAGAAGUGGGUGAGCCAGGGUCUGAGUUUCACAUUUGAACCAAAUAAAAUGCUGUCAAGAGAAAA